UCUCGGCCGCCGGCGGAAUCUGGGAACCCGAGGCCAUCACGUCUCCAUGUCUGCGGGUUUCUGUGAGGGCGUGUGGUUCUCCCUGUGGGUCCCUGGCGCUCUGUUCCGGUUUCUGUCUGUCCCUGUGGGUCUCUGCCUCCCCCGCCCCCUCUCCCUUUCCGCGGCACUCGUCCUUCCCCCAGCACCUUCCCCCCGGCCCGUGGGUCCGUAUUUCUCCAUUGACUUCCCUUUGUGAGUUUCUGAUCCCCUCUUUGCUAGUCUCUCUCGUUAUGUGUUUCGUUGUGUCUGUGUUUCUCCACCAGCCUCCCUCUAUCUGCAUGCGGGUCUCUGACUCCGCUGACCUCUCACCAUGGAUUUGUGUUUCUCAAUUUGUCUCUGAUCCCUGAGGACGUGUAUUCCGUUUCUCUGGUCUCUGCCUUCCUCAUCACAUCCAUAUAGCCUCAGACCCUACCCUUCCUCCUUAACACUUCCCCCCAUCCUUCGCAGGCCACCAGCAGAACCCACCAGACAGAAGCUCCGUGCUCUGCCUGGCUGGUCACUGCCUGGCACGUACUAGACACUCCUUAUACACGCAUUAGUCCAUUUCCUGUGCAGCUGUAUUGGCCCUACGUGAAAGAUGCGAGCUUGGCCCACACCUUAGCUAAUUUUGUUUCUCACUAAAGCAGAAUGGGGAAAGCGAUUUGACUGCCUCCAUUCGUGGGGCACUUGAGAUGUGUCCCUGUAAGUCUUCUCACAGAACACAUGACUGGAUCUCCUCCUCGUGAAUGACACCUCAUUUCCUUCAUGUUUCUUAAGUCCGUCAGGUGCCAUAAGAUUCUGGAAUUUAGUGGCCACAACUUGUACUUUUGGGGAUUUUUCAGACUUGGUGUUGAAAGGGGAAAACAGGAAUAUAAUAGAAAGCGUGGACUAGCGUUCGACCUGGGCAGGAGUCCUCCGUAAUUAUGUGAGCAGAGACCCCUGCAUCUGUCCGACCGCAGCCUUUCCGUCACUGAGCCAGUUAUGACAGUAUUGGCUCUGCAGGGCUGUGUGAGGAUUAAAGGACCGCACACAUGUAAAGAGCAUGGCACUGCCUAGCACAACAGGAGGUGCCAGUUGUCUUCCCGUUACCUUUGCAGUUUUGAGGUCCUGUAACCAGAGCAGCUGAGGAUUCAAACCUCGUAGUACGAAGGUCUGUAUGAGACAAGAAAGGAAAGGUAACAGAGGAGCAUUUCUAUUUCCUGAUCCUUUUCCAUAGCUGUUUCCAGAGAAAUUUACUGAUGUCAAUUCUGUGCUUUUGACACAGGGUUGGUGCAAAGAUCCACGCAACUGAUGCAGGCUAGUGUAGCUAUCUAGUGUAGGCUCUGGAGCCAGCCUGCCUGGGUUUGAAUCCGCCUUUUACUAGUCUUGGGCAGUGAUUGAUGAGGGAGACAAAGCCUCUUCUGGACUGCCCCUCAGAGCCAGGGUGGCCUGGGCCUGGGAGCCACUGGGACUGCAAAUCUGGUUUGCCACCUGGUGGCACCAGGAACAAUUGUUCUCGGUGUCCACUGUCCUGAGGAAUUGGGACUCUGGGUUCAAUCCAGUUGCUCUGCGGUUUGUGCUCUUAGAGCACAGGAUGAUGCCCAUGGGGAUGUGGUCCUCAUAGGAGAGGGGAGCAGGGCCGAGGGAAUUAGCGUGUGGACGUGCUCGGAGUACCCAGUCCACGCCGUUCCCCUGGAUAAUAGUCACUGCUUCUUUUCAUGAAGGUGGGAUAUCACCCCAUAUCCAUCUCUCCAGUCUCUACCCUGUCCCCAGAAAAAGCCCAGAGGGCAAGGGAGAAUCUGUAGAGGUUCCAGCCUUCCCAGACCACUCUCAGGACUGGGCUGUGCUCCUCCCCAGCUGAAUCCACCACCACAGGAUAAUGGGGGGUCCGGGUUGCUCUCCGGCGGCCUCCCUCGGAAGUGUUCCGUCUUCCACCUGUUCGUGGCCUGCCUCUCGCUGGGCUUCUUCUCCCUACUCUGGCUGCAGCUCAGCUGCUCUGGGGACGUGGCCCGGGCAGUCAGGGGACAAGGGCAGGAGACCUCGGGCCCUCCCCGUGCCUGCCCCCCAGAGCCGCCCCCUGAGCACUGGGAAGAAGACGCAUCCUGGGGCCCCCACCGCCUGGCAGUGCUGGUGCCCUUCCGCGAACGCUUCGAGGAGCUCCUGGUCUUCGUGCCCCACAUGCGCCGCUUCCUGAGCAGGAAGAAGAUCCGGCACCACAUCUACGUGCUCAACCAGGUGGACCACUUCAGGUUCAACCGGGCAGCGCUCAUCAACGUGGGCUUCCUGGAGAGCAGCAACAGCACGGACUACAUUGCCAUGCACGACGUUGACCUGCUCCCUCUCAACGAGGAGCUGGACUAUGGCUUUCCUGAGGCUGGGCCCUUCCACGUGGCCUCCCCGGAGCUCCACCCUCUCUACCACUACAAGACCUAUGUCGGCGGCAUCCUGCUGCUCUCCAAGCAGCACUACCGGCUGUGCAAUGGGAUGUCCAACCGCUUCUGGGGCUGGGGCCGCGAGGACGACGAGUUCUACCGGCGCAUUAAGGGAGCUGGGCUCCAGCUUUUCCGCCCCUCGGGAAUCACAACUGGGUACAAGACAUUUCGCCACCUGCAUGACCCAGCCUGGCGGAAGAGGGACCAGAAGCGCAUCGCAGCUCAAAAACAGGAGCAGUUCAAGGUGGACAGGGAGGGAGGCCUGAACACUGUGAAGUACCAUGUGGCUUCCCGCACUGCCCUGUCUGUGGGCGGGGCCCCCUGCACUGUCCUCAACAUCAUGUUGGACUGUGACAAGACCGCCACACCCUGGUGCACAUUCAGCUGAGCUGGAUGGACAGUGAGGAAGCCUGUACCUACAGGCCAUAUUGCUCAGGCUCAGGACAAGGCCUCAGGUCGUGGGCCCAGCUCUGACAGGAUGUGGAGUGGCCAGGACCAAGACAGCAAGCUACGCAAUUGCAGCCACCCGGCCGCCAAGGCAGGCUUGGGCUGGGCCAGGACACGUGGGGUGCCUGGGACGCUGCUUGCCAUGCACAGUGAUCAGAGAGAGGCUGGGGUGUGUCCUGUCCGGGACCCCCCCUGCCUUCCUGCUCACCCUACUCUGACCUCCUUCACGUGCCCAGGCCUGUGGGUAGUGGGGAGGGCUGAACAGGACAACCUCUCAUCACCCCCACUUUUGUUCCUUCCUGCUGGGCUGCCUCGUGCAGAGACACAGUGUAGGGGCCAUGCAGCUGGCGUAGGUGGCAGUUGGGCCUGGUGAGGGUUAGGACUUCAGAAACCAGAGCACAAGCCCCACAGAGGGGGAACAGCCAGCACCGCUCUAGCUGGUUGUUGCCAUGCCGGAAUGUGGGCCUAGUGUUGCCAGAUCUUCUGAUUUUUCGAAAGAAACUAGAAUGCUGGAUUCUUAAGUGAUAUCUUCUGAUUUUUUAAAUGAUAGCACCUAAAUGAAACUUUCAAAAAGUA